ACUGCAGCUGCUGCUGCCUGCUGGUUGCCGCGUCUUCCCGGAGGCGACUGCUGGAAGCUGCAGGGAACAGCUGCGGUGCUCUGCCAUAUUGUGUCUUCCCCGGCCGGUCCCUCGCCUCCCGGCCGAGCUGACGGUGAGUCCCGGGCGGAGCGGUCCCCUCCAGGGUCGGCGCUCCCCGCCCCAGCCCGCGGCGCAGCUCCCGGGCGCGGAGGCAGCGCGAGCGACCCGCGCCAGGCGUGGGGCGCGGAGGCGGCUGUCCCGUGACGCGCCCGGACAUUUUUGUCCAGUGAGGAAUUUGCGCCGGCGCGGGGGUGUCCCCGGCGCGCGUAUCGGGUGGUGUGUGGGCUCCGGGGGAUGUCGAACUGAGGGGAGUGUGGCUUGUGAGGAGUUAGGAGUUUUUCCUGAGAGGUAAUGACCGCCCGGGAGGGGCUGUCGCGCGGCGGAAACCGCGGCGAGGGGUGUCGUCUCUCCGGGAAGGCGUGGAGGGGGCCCCAAGGACCCUCAGGGCUCGGCUCGGGGCUGGAAUCUGCUGUUAGGGAAGUACCCCAAGCACCUCGGAGCCUUUGCAACGCCCCCUCCUCUGGCUUGAAGUGGAGCGAGACAUGUCGGGCUCGGAGUCCUCGUCCGGCCCCAGUUGGGACUGGCUGGGCCCCGCCAAGUAGUGCACGGGGAGGUGCCGGGGGCGGCCGGGCGUUGUGGUGGGCAGAGGCGGGUCCCGGGUGUGUGUGGGAGCGACCCCGGCACCCUCUCGCCCCUCCACCGCCUCGAGGGGGCCUCAGAGGGUGGCUGUCUUGGGAGCUACUGUUUCAGCGCUGCAAUAUGGACACUUCCUGUUCGCCGCCUCCUUUGGGGCCGUGGUUACCUUUGCCUUUUAGUCCUCUUUCCUGGCAAGGUGAGAGGUCUGCGGUGGAAGAGGCCUUCAGCCUUUCAAGUUUGCCCCACUGCAGCAGCAGCCUGUGUGGAACCCGGCAGGACGGUGGUAGUUAGCGGAAAGCAGCCCAUGUGCUCCGUGCUCCAUCCUCCACUACUUAACUCCACCCCCUUUUGCACCUUUGCAAAAUGCCUCUUUUUCCACUGCAUCUCUCGGGAGUUGGGGUGUCUGCUUCGCUGACGACCCACACUCUCGCAGUGUUCUUGCACUGGAUUUCUGCUUUAAAGUCUUUUUACAGCAGUCUCUGAACUUCAUUUUCUCCCUACUGGGAAAAAAGAGUUUUAGCGUGCAAAGAAAUGACCACAGACUUUCUUUCUCCUACCCCAACUCCGAGGUGAGGGGAGGAGGGCAGUUAAGUAUUUACAGUUGGUUGAAGCCAUGGAUAACAGAACCCACAGAUGCAGAGGGCUGACUGUACAAGUCUGUCAAAAAACCAAACUGCUGGUUGGCUAAUAAUUGGUCACUGUAUGACUUAUAGUACAGGUGAUAUUACUUCUGAUUCUAGAUGAUCUUUUGUGGUACUGCUUUUUGAAAUCCGUGUUUCUGUGAAACGGAGGAGGAUUGUGUACUAGAGACUCAUCUUGAUGUAUUUGGUCUUUAUGCAGAAAAUAUCAGCAGCAUGGUGAACCACGUACCUGGAUCAAGGUACCAAGUACCUUCAGCUUUCUGCUGAAAACAACCUAAAAUGCUGGAUAAAAUAAAAUCUUAAAUGCAUCAGUGCUCUGGCGCAAAGGGGAGAGUACUUAGGCCAGGCUGAAUUCUGAAUCUGGCUAUUGCUUUGAGGAUAUUUGCCAAAUCAGAACUGUAAGAGUAAAUGGGUCCAGUAAUUGGAAUGACUCCAGAUAAGAGAGCUGAAACCCCAGGAGCUGAAAAGAUUGCAGGAUUAAGCCAGAUUUACAAAAUGGGAAGCUUGCCUGAAGCUGUUGAUGCUGCCAGGCCGAAGGCCACUCUAGUGGACAGUGAGUCAGCAGAUGAUGAACUCACAAACUUGAACUGGCUUCAUGAAAGCACUAAUCUUCUAACAAACUUCAGCCUCGGAAGUGAGGGUCUUCCAAUUGUUAGUCCAUUGUAUGACAUAGAGGGAGAUGAUGUGCCAUCCUUUGGACCAGCUUGCUACCAGAACCCAGAAAAAAAAUCAGCGACUUCAAAGCCCCCAUACUCCUUUAGUCUUCUCAUUUAUAUGGCCAUUGAGCACUCUCCAAAUAAAUGUUUGCCUGUCAAAGAAAUUUAUAGCUGGAUUCUGGACCAUUUUCCAUAUUUUGCUACUGCACCAACAGGCUGGAAGAAUUCUGUUCGACAUAAUCUGUCCCUGAAUAAAUGUUUUCAGAAAGUGGAAAGAAGCCAUGGCAAGGUUAAUGGAAAAGGUUCCUUAUGGUGUGUUGAUCCGGAAUAUAAACCCAAUCUUAUCCAGGCACUGAAGAAGCAACCUUUUUCUUCAGCAUCUUCACAAAAUGGUUCUUUAUCACCUCACUAUUUAAGCUCUGUAAUCAAGCAGAACCAGGUGCGAAACCUCAAAGAAUCUGAUAUUGAUGCUGCUGCUGCAAUGAUGCUUUUAAAUACUUCUAUAGAACAAGGAAUUUUAGAAUGUGAGAAGCCUCUUCCUCUUAAAACAGCAUUGCAAAAAAAGAGGAGUUACGGCAAUGCAUUUCAUCAUCCCAGUGCUGUACGAUUACAAGAGAGUGAUUCUUUAGCCACCAGCAUUGAUCCAAAAGAAGAUCACAAUUACAGUGCAAGUAGCAUGGCAGCACAGCGUUGUGCAUCCAGGUCUAGCGUGUCUUCCCUGUCUUCUGUGGAUGAGGUAUAUGAAUUUAUCCCAAAGAAUAGUCACGUGGGAAGUGAUGGCAGUGAAGGAUUUCACAGUGAAGAAGAUACAGACGUUGAUUAUGAAGAUGAUCCUCUUGGAGACAGUGGCUAUGCAUCACAGCCUUGUGCAAAAAUCUCUGAAAAAGGGCAGUCAGGCAAAAAGAUGCGAAAACAGACAUGUCAAGAAAUUGAUGAGGAGCUCAAAGAGGCAGCUGGAUCUCUGCUCCACCUUGCUGGAAUUCGUACAUGUUUAGGUUCCCUAAUAAGUACUGCAAAGACACAAAAUCAAAAGCAACGGAAAAAAUAGAAAUACUUAAAGUGUGGCAAUACUCUUUCACUUAAUUCUUUACAAGGGAUAUCAAAGCCAUAAUGGACUUCAUUAGUUUUAGGGUAGGGAAGGGAUACUAAUUACUUAUUUCUUUCAAAACAUUUUUGGUUUUUGGUUUUUAAAAUUUUUAUUAAACAAUUGCUGUUAGGAUCAUGCCUGAUCAGAAAUACAUGAUGUGAAGUCCUAAAAGCAUAAUUUUUGUGAUAAAUGUGUCCAAGAUUUGAAAAUUUUUAUAUAAGAAAAUCCCCAGCCUCUGUCUUAAACUUGUGGGACAAAAAUCCUUUCUUCUGUUAAUAUGUCAGAAUGUAAGAUUUGGCAACUCGAUAAAUUUUUUUCAUUUUCUUUUCCAAUCUGUAACUAUAGUUACUGAACCAGCUAAAAAUUUUGCUGAUGUAUUUUUCAUAUACUUCUCUCCUGACACGCAAUCCGGUAACAUAAGAUUGAAAUUUUUUUACUUUGUCUUAAUUUGUUUCUAAUUUUUUUUUUGUUGUCGUGUGAGCAAAGACAAACAUAAAUUGAAAAACAUCCUGAUGUUUAGAAAGUUUCUUUUGGUUACGUAGGUAGAGAAUACAACAAAGAGUUCUAAGACUUAGAAAAGACAAUUUUGUGGUGUCAUUUCAUCCAAGAACACUCCCAAUUCCUAUUAGAAUGGUAGCUUUGAAGUGUUUUUACUUCAGAGAUCCUGCAUAGCAUUUAUUGGGGCCUUUUAUUCUUUCCCAAAGUGCUUUGCAAACAUUAAGUUUUAGCCACUAGCUGCCUUUGUUGAGUAUAAGUUAUCCAGUGAGAGGAUAUAGCCAAUUAAGUGUGUUAUGGAGUACACCCAUUUUGACACACUUGUAAUAAGAGAAUCUUUCAUUUGCCUGCCAUGUGUACUGUAUUAUGAGAAUCUUAUAAUCGGAAUGGAGUGAAAUGAAACAUUUUGAGUACUGAUGGCAUGUUAUCAUACAUAAAGUAGGUCAUUUAGGAAAAAACUUCUGUCCAAGCUUUGUAUGAAUUAAAUUCAUAAGUAUACCAAAUUAAAUCUUAAUAGAUUUAAUGCAAUUUUACAGACACAAUACCUUCAUGAAUUUCAAAAUUCAUAUAAAAUUUGAUCUUAUGCAAUACACCUUUUUGAGGAGGCAGUGUAACAACCUAUAGUGCCAUUGAUCCAUGAGAAAAAGAUUUUCUGGUACUACUCCAAAAGUGCUUUGACUAAGUAUCUUAACUAUUUGAACAGUCUGCUUAUAUGAGACAGUUUUUCAUAGUAUCAUUUGUAUAAUUUGAUUAGAUUAUUCAGAAACAAUAGGAUGCUAAACUAAUUCAUUGUAUCUUUUUUUUACAAUGGUGGAAGCAACUUUCUGAAAGUUCAGUCUUAUGCUACAUCCUAAGUCAUAGACAAUGACCUUGUUUUCAUUAUUCUGAUAGAUUGUAUACAUAUGUACACAUACAUAUACACAUAUGCACAGUCAAGGUCAUGAUGUUGAUUUGCUUUCAGCUGUUUCUGUGAUUAUAAAGCAUUUUUUAAGAGACAAAUUUUAACUUUUAAUUUUUAUUUUGGCAAAACUGUCAAAUGAGAAAAAUGAUUUUAAAAACUUUUUUUUCAAUUGACAAGACUUUAAGUCAGGGAUAACAGUAUUAAUGUUCUCUGUUCUGUUUCCAUGUUAAAUUUAAUUUAACCUGGAUAGCCACAUUAAUGAAUUGGUGCUGUCAAAAUAUAGUAAUUUUUAAAUUUGUUAAUAAUGAAAACCCUUAAGCAUGCAGGAUGAGGUAUUUGGGUUUUUUUUUUAGAUCGAUCACAUCUACAGAAAAUGGCUAAACCAAGUUAACUUUUAUUAUAGACAGUGAAUAAAACACCAAAAACCCAAAAAUGCUUUAACCACAGUAUAAAUAAUAGAUUAUACACAUCAUCUUAAUAACUAUUUUUAAGUUAUUUACCAUAGCCUCUGUAUAGACCUUAGGAACAGUGUUUCAGUGAUCUGGCACCAGUUUAUUUUGUUCUGCUGAAAUUCUGUAUCACAAAUGUGCUACCUGGUUUUUGUCCAUUAGAUAAUUACUCUUUAUAAGGAAAGGAAAGAGAAGCAGAGUUAGUUCCAGCUCUAAUAGGGAUCUUCAAAGUUAUUUUGUCUUGAUGUAUGUAACAGUAAUUCUUUACAUCUUUUGAUUUUUCUCUUCCUUUUUAUUCACUCUUCCCACGAAUUUAAAUGUUUAAGUUAUAUUCAUCACUAGCAAGGAUGAUAAACACUUGUGCACUGAAAGCUAACAGGGAGAGGUUACACAAUAUUUUACAGUUUCUUAAACAUAAUUUAAUGCAUCACCUUCCACUUGCUAACAUACCAAGUCAGUUAUUUUCAAGGGAAGAACCUUUUAAAUUAUGGUCCUCCAUUUACUACUUCCACUGAGAGUAUGCUCUCAUUCCUCAGGUGUUUUGAGAAACAUGACUAAUAACCACACAAUUAAGUAGAGUCAUUCCAAGUCCUAUGGCCUGGAAAUUGUAUUCCCUAUAAUAUACAAAUUUUCCUGUAAUAAAGUCAACUUAGAAACUCCAAGGAGGUUACAUGUUUUCCAACAUAUCCUAAAAACUGUGAUAUAAGCUAACAUAUAAUUUGCCUUACGUCAAAAGAAUAUGUUUUGUUGCAGCUGAUUCCAGUUUAUAAUAGAUCCCUAGUAAAAAGCUUUGAUUCAACACAAUUGUUCAUCUUCACAUCCCAAACAGAAUCACUGUUUCUUGAAUAUAUAUUUUUGAAGUUUUUUUGUGCAAUAUAUUACUAAAUCAGUUAUUAUUUUACUUUUCCAAAUUCAGAGAAAGAAAACAGAUUACCUGAAUUCAUGGAAAAGGUGGAUCACCUCCCUUUUUCCACCUUCAAGCCUUUCCUGUCCUCAUAGCCAGCAUGACUUCUUUUAACUUGGAUUCCUUUGUAUAUAGUAAAGUUUAGUAUAUAUAUAUUUUUUUCUUUUUGCUACUUUCUGAGGCAUUAUGUAAAGGGCUCAUACUAGAUGUUCAGUUAAAUAUACUUUAGCACAAAGUCAAACUAGAGAAUGUGUUAAGGAGGGAAUGUAUAUGUCUUGGUAGACCAGGAGGCCUUUGCCAGCAAUUUAAGCAACAGAUGUGAAUACUUCACAAAGCUGUAAAGACCAUUGUCUUAAAUACUACAACAACUUAACACCCUUUUGUGAAGAUCACAGCAUUUAUCUAAGAAACUGUGAGGCUUUCUGGUUUACAUAUAUCUUACAGGUGUUUUUUUGUAUUUUUUUUUUUUUUUAGUUUGAAAUGUGUAAGCUUUGAUUUAAACCAAGUUUACUUCAGUAUGUUAAUGAUGUAGUAAAAAUAUUUAUUGAAAGGUGAAUUCGAGUAUUUUAAUGUUAUACCUGCCAUUUUUUUUCUUAAAGCAUAUUCUUUGCAUCUAACUGCCAGUGCCAUUGUCAAAACUUAUUUUUUAAAUCGUUGUACAUUUCUUAUUAAACUAAGUGCUUAAUUUUAAAGUAUUAUGUUGCCAUCAUAUAGUGUAUAAAAAUGUAUAAUUGCCAAUUGAUUGUAACUAUUAUUUAUUUUUAAAUGAAAGUGUAAGAAUGCUUUCUGAUUCAACAAAUUUGUUAUCAAACUGUUUCCUUAUCCUCUUUUCUGAUGUAGCAUAAAAAUUGUCCCGGUUUGAGUUAUAACUGCCAGUAGAUGACCAGUCACAAGUGAACCACUUCUCAGUUGCCAAUCUUUGCUCAUAUUAAAAACAACUUACAAAUACUUAGUUUUUGUAUCUAAUCUCUGAUUAUUAAAAUGUUUAUAAAGUUUAUUUUUACCAAAGAGAUGCAAUUCAUUAUGAGAAAGUAUUGCAUAAUAAAUUUUGUUUUAUAACUUUU